GCGGCCGCGCGCUUGGGCGGCGGAGGCUGCAGCUACCUCGGCGCCGGCUCGGCUCUAGGACGUGUCGGGCUGCACGGGUCGGGGGCGGCUCCCUGCUGCUUCCGAGCCUAGCCGCCUGGCCUUCGGCAUUUGCAGGCAGACACACUGCCCUCCAGAAACGAUGGGUGUCGCUAGAUCCAGCUGGGACUCUGCCAGCCUCCGGCACUCAGUCUAAGAGAAGGGCCAUCUUCCAGCCCUGCUGUCCCUGCCUGUCAUGGCCACAUUCGGCUGCUGUCUGCAUGUCUGGGGACACAGGGCACCCAGCCCCAGCCCUGAGAAGUUAAGCCAGGCCUUCUGGCUCAGUUCCACAGGGGCACUCCAGACCCCAGGCCCCUUUCAGAGCAAAAGCAACUGAUGCUAUGGGAGAAGCCCCUGCCCACCUGUCCACUCGCCUGGCACUGCCCACUCUGAGACCCAUGCACUGGGUUCCCCUGGAGGUGCCAACCCUGUGAGUCCCUCCCUGUCCCCUGACGCUGAGAAGGCCCUGCCAACCCCCACCAUGUGUGAGGUGAUGCCCACAAUCAAUGAGGGGGACCGCCUGGGUCCCCCUCAUGGCGCCGAUGCUGACGCCAACUUCGAGCAGCUGAUGGUGAACAUGCUGGACGAGCGGGAGAAGUUGCUGGAGUCUCUUCGGGAGAGUCAGGAGACCUUGGCGGCCACACAGAGCCGGCUCCAGGAUGCCAUACACGAGCGGGACCAGCUCCAGCGCCACCUUAACUCCGCCCUCCCCCAGGAAUUUGCCACCUUAACCCGGGAGCUGAGCAUGUGUCGGGAGCAGCUUCUAGAGCGGGAGGAAGAGAUAUCAGAACUGAAAGCAGAACGGAAUAACACACGGCUGCUUCUGGAACAUCUGGAGUGCCUGGUGUCCCGCCAUGAACGGUCACUGCGGAUGACUGUGGUGAAGCGCCAGGCCCAGUCACCUUCGGGGGUCUCCAGUGAGGUGGAGGUGCUGAAGGCCCUCAAGUCACUGUUUGAGCACCACAAGGCCCUGGAUGAGAAGGUGCGAGAGCGGCUCCGGGCAGCGCUGGAGCGAGUCACCACCUUGGAGGAGCAGCUGGCAGGUGCCCACCAGCAGGUGUCUGCCCUGCAGCAGGGGGCAGGGGUGCGGGAUGGAGCGGCAGAAGAGGAGGGGACUGUGGAGCUGGGGCCGAAACGCCUGUGGAAGGAGGAUACGGGCCGGGUAGAGGAGCUGCAGGAGCUCCUGGAGAAGCAGAACUUUGAGUUGAGCCAGGCCCGGGAGCGACUGGUCACCCUAACAACAACCGUGACUGAACUCGAGGAGGACCUGGGCACGGCCCGCCGGGACCUCAUCAAGUCGGAGGAGCUGAGCAGCAAGCAUCAGCGGGACCUCCGGGAGGCUCUGGCCCAGAAGGAGGACAUGGAAGAGCGGAUUACUACACUGGAGAAGCGCUACCUGGCUGCUCAGCGUGAGGCAACAUCCAUCCAUGACCUCAAUGACAAGCUGGAGAAUGAGCUGGCCAACAAGGAGUCCCUGCACCGCCAGUGUGAGGAGAAGGCCCGACACCUGCAGGAGCUGCUGGAGGUGGCAGAGCAGAAGCUGCAGCAGACGAUGCGCAAGGCAGAGACGCUGCCAGAGGUGGAGGCUGAGCUGGCCCAGAGAAUUGCAGCCCUCACCAAGGCUGAAGAACGGCAUGGCAACAUUGAGGAGCACCUGCGGCAGCUGGAGGGACAGCUGGAGGAGAAGAACCAGGAGCUGGCACGGGUGCGCCAGCGGGAAAAGAUGAAUGAGGACCACAACAAGCGGCUGUCGGACACAGUGGACCGGCUGCUCAGCGAGUCCAACGAGCGUCUGCAGCUCCACCUGAAGGAGCGCAUGGCUGCCCUGGAGGAGAAGGGCCGCCUGUCUGAAGAGAUUGAGAAGCUGCGCCAAGAGGUGGACCAGCUGAAGGGCCGAGGGGGGCCGUUUGUGGAUGGCGUCCACUCCAGGUCGCACAUGGGCAGUGCAGCAGACGUGCGGUUCUCCCUGGGCACAACCACACACGCACCCCCAGGCGUGCAUCGCCGCUACUCGGCAUUGAGGGAAGAGUCUGCCAAGGACUGGGAGACUUCUCCACUGCCUGGGAUGCUGGCCCCGGCAGCUGGCCCUGCCUUUGACAGUGACCCUGAGAUCUCCGACGUGGAUGAGGAUGAGCCAGGGGGUCUGGUGGGCUCUGCGGAUGUUGUCUCCCCCAGCGGCCACUCAGAUGCCCAGACCCUGGCCAUGAUGCUGCAGGAGCAGCUGGAUGCCAUCAAUGAGGAAAUCAGGAUGAUUCAGGAAGAGAAGGAGUCCACGGAGCUCCGCGCGGAGGAGAUUGAGACGCGUGUAACCAGUGGCAGCAUGGAAGCCCUAAACCUGAAGCAGCUGCGCAAGCGUGGUUCCAUCCCCACCUCUCUGACGGCCCUGUCCCUGGCCAGCGCGUCCCCACCACUCAGCGGCCGCUCCACACCUAAGCUCACCUCCCGCAGUGCUGCCCAGGACCUGGACCGAAUGGGGGUCAUGACCCUGCCCAGUGACUUAAGAAAGCAUAGGAGGAAGCUGCUGUCGCCAGUGUCUCGGGAAGAGAACCGAGAGGAUAAAGCCACCAUAAAAUGUGAGACUUCUCCUCCUUCCUCACCCAGGACGCUGCGGCUAGAGAAGCUUGGCCACCCAGCCCUGAGCCAGGAAGAAGGCAAGAGUGCCUUGGAGGAUCAGGGCAGCAACCCCAGCAGCAGCAACAGCAGCCAGGACUCCCUGCACAAGGGCGCCAAGCGCAAGGGCAUCAAGUCGUCCAUUGGCCGCCUGUUUGGGAAGAAGGAGAAGGGCAGGCUGAUCCAGCUGAGUCGGGAUGGAGCCACAGGCCAUGUUCUGCUAACAGACUCCGAAUUCAGUAUGCAGGAGCCUAUGGUGCCUGCCAAGCUGGGGACCCAGGCAGAGAAGGACCGGCGGCUAAAGAAGAAACACCAGCUGCUUGAAGAUGCCCGCAGGAAAGGAAUGCCCUUUGCCCAGUGGGAUGGUCCUACUGUGGUCUCCUGGUUGGAGCUCUGGGUGGGGAUGCCUGCCUGGUAUGUGGCAGCCUGCCGGGCCAACGUCAAGAGUGGUGCCAUCAUGUCCGCUCUGUCGGACACAGAGAUCCAGCGGGAGAUCGGCAUCAGCAAUGCCCUGCACCGGCUCAAGCUCCGCCUGGCCAUUCAGGAGAUGGUGUCAUUGACCAGCCCCUCUGCCCCACCCACCUCCAGGACUUCUUCUGGGAAUGUCUGGGUCACCCAUGAAGAGAUGGAAACUCUGGAAACAUCUACUAAAACAGACAGUGAGGAGGGCAGCUGGGCUCAGACCCUGGCCUAUGGGGACAUGAACCAUGAGUGGAUUGGGAAUGAAUGGCUACCCAGCCUGGGGCUCCCGCAGUACCGCAGCUACUUCAUGGAGUGCCUGGUGGACGCCCGCAUGCUGGACCACCUCACCAAGAAGGACCUGCGGGUCCACCUGAAGAUGGUGGACAGCUUCCAUCGAACCAGUCUUCAGUAUGGCAUCAUGUGUCUGAAGAGGCUGAAUUAUGACCGGAAGGAGCUGGAGAAGAGGCGAGAGGAGAGCCAGCAUGAGAUCAAGGAUGUGUUAGUCUGGACCAACGACCAGGUGGUUCAUUGGGUCCAGUCUAUUGGGCUCCGGGACUACGCAGGAAACCUGCAUGAGAGUGGUGUGCAUGGAGCCUUGCUGGCCCUGGACGAGAACUUCGACCACAACACACUGGCCCUGAUCCUCCAGAUCCCCACACAGAACACCCAGGCACGCCAAGUGAUGGAAAGAGAGUUCAAUAACCUGUUGGCCUUGGGCACAGACCGGAAGCUGGAUGACGGGGAUGACAAGGUGUUUCGCCGCGCGCCCUCCUGGAGGAAGCGCUUCCGGCCGCGGGAGCACCACGGUCGCGGCGGCAUGCUCAGCGCUUCCGCGGAGACCCUCCCGGCGGGCUUCCGUGUGUCCACCCUGGGGACCCUGCAGCCCCCACCGGCCCCGCCAAAGAAGAUCAUGCCUGAAGCUGGGACGGCGGGGUCGCAGAGACUGGAGACCUCCACGGUUCGGACCUACUCCUGCUGACCCCCCAUCCUCCCGCCCCGGGUCUGACGGGGGAGUGCCCGUGGCUCGGGCUCACUCCCACUAUCUCUACGGACACAUGCUCUCCGCCUUCCGGGACUAGCCAUGGCCCCCAGGGCUGGCUUCCUCCUUCUGGGUUUCACAGGCUCCUCUGGCCCUGACCCCUCUUGCUCGUUCCCCUUCCUUCCGCAGCUCCUAGUCUCGUCCGUGACUUUCCGGUUGCCCUGGAUCUCAGAAUAUAUUCGUCCACCCCCUCGGCACCCCAUUACCCCGAGUCCCACCGUGUGUCCGUUGUAAGUCCGGUGGAUGUGGCUGGGGUUUCCUGGUAUUGUGGAGGCACCCAGGUUGUCCAUGCUUGGGAUUCUGGGGGAAGGAGAGAAGGGCAGCUCAGGGUGGAUGUGAAGCCACCCUUCCUCUUCUGGACCCAGCCUGGUCUGCACUGCAACCUCCACCAGGACCAGGAUCCUGGGCCACAGGCUGGGAUGGUCCUUCCAAGAAAGGGUCAUUUCAGACGCAGCCCUGCUUGGGCUAUUCAAUCUUAGGGUGUCUAUCCACGUCUGGCUGUGCCAAAUGGUCUGGCAGCUGGUUUUGGCAUCCCCAGCAUCACCACUCUCCCAACCCAUCACCGUGACUGCAGUUCCUGCCCCCAUUCUCUUGGGGUCAGGGAGGGGCUGGGAAGGGCUACUGAAGGCCCCAUUCUCCCACAGGAUGGUGAGGCUGGGAGGAGGAAGACUGAGGUAGAGAUUCCAGGCCCUGGCAUAAGCUGAAUCCCAAAUUUGAGUUUGGGAAGAACCAGAGAGAAAUGGAUCCCUGAGCUCUGAGCCAAGGGUGAGGAUGGGGAAACUCUAAGCUCCCACCUAAUAAGAAGCAUAGGCAGACCAGCCAGAGGGAGAGCCAAUGGCCUCUGGUAGCCUUAAGCCCAAAGGGCAGUGGGAAUGUCCCCUGCCCCAACCAUCGGGUGGAGCUCCUGCUGGGCUAUGGGGAAGGGAGGUUGUGCGGAUCUUGACUCUAGGGCAGAACAGAUCUAACCAUGCAUUGCUAGCUCUGCUCCCAGCAUCCCUUCCCCUUCUCUCCUCCUCUGCCUCACUUCUUUAGUAAUCCCAACCCUAUAAAAAUGAACCUAAUGGGUGGAUUGAAUAUACAUUGAGCCCAAAGUCAAGUUUGGGGAAAAGGCAGACUAAGGCCUCCUUUCUCUGACCUCCCAGGAAGAAAAUAGCUUCUCCUACAGUGAUUCAUGUCCCAGGUCCAGGAAAUCCAAUGUUGGUGAAGGCAGCCACUCUCUUGCUUGUCCCCAAAUCACCUAACCCUCAUCCAGGGCUAUUUUGGUGGGCAGGGACUGCCUCCUCCCGGAAUUCCUAAGAUCCGCCCAGCUGCCACCAUUUUCAUUGCUUUCCCCAGCAGCAUGAUGGGAACCCAAGCUGAGGGAUACAGGUCCUGAUUUGGUAGGAAUAUUAUUCCCAAGAAAUACCCGCUCCUCACCUACUCCCUCAUCCUACCAAGGUGCCUGAAAAUGUUCAAGACUUAUGUUCAGGGUGGGAUGAUGGAACCGAGGGCUUCAUCAAAGUGAGAGGAAAGGAAAAGCAUCUGGCAUGUGUUUCUUGGAUAGGGGCCAGUGCAGUGCCAUCCUACAGGUGGCUGGAGCAGCUGCUUUGCAACCUGAUCACCUUGAGUUCUGAGCAGGGACUAGGCUUGCAGGUGAGAUAAUGGGCCAGGGCACCCAGUCCAGAAGGAGCAAUGGCACCUGGGCAGUGCCAGGGCUUAAAGCCCGCUGCUCCUUUUCGGUAGAGGAGAGGCCCAUCACUGGUGUGGUGGGGUGGGCUCUCCCUUAGGCUUGGGCAAGGCAGCCACCUGCCCUUGCUCUCCCUUAGUGUUCCCUGGCCUCCCUGCCAUCAGGUUGCUGGGAGUGGAGAUGGAGGGAUUAUUGAGCAGAAAAUGAGUUGGAUGGAGAUAAACAGCUCCCAUCCCUGGGUAAUGGAUGGUAAGAUGAUGGAGAUUCCUAAGAUUGGUGGAGUUGGGCAAUGCAUAGCCAUCUGACUCCUUCAGGGUGCUCUUGAUGGGCUGGCUGUAAGGGAGACUCAGUCCCAGCCUCUCCCCUCUACAACUCCUGCCACUGUUGGCCAUGUCGUAAGGCAGCAGCUGUGCCAGGAUAGCUGGGUCCAUUCAGAGCACCUUGAGAAGUGUUGCAGGGAGGUGUUAAGAAGAGAACUCUGUGCAAACAGUGAUGGAAGGCUGUUGUCUUGGUGUAUCCCUUGCCUCAUAGUCAAUAUAUUUUUUUUUUGGCGAGUCACCAGUGACCCGAGCCCUCCACACCAGCCUCCUGUAUCUCAUCAGGUCCCUUCUCAGUACUGUAUUUGCUCAGUGCAUCAGGAAUGGGUGUAUGGGUGUGUGUGGGUGGGUGUGAGUGUGGGUGUGUACGUACCAAUAAACAACCUGGUUUUAAGACAAUGUA